AGCUUUGCAGUCGCUGCCUUCUCGCGCCUGACCAUGCACCCCUGCAUCUUCCUGCUGGGCCACAGGCGAGCGCUUUAUUUCUGGAGCUGAGGGCUAAAACUUUUUUGACUUUUCUUCUCCUCAACAUCUGAAUCAUGCCAUGUGCCCAGAGGAGCUGGCUUGCAAACCUUUCCGUGGUGGCUCAGCUCCUUAACUUUGGGGCGCUUUGCUAUGGGAGACAGCCUCAGCCAGGCCCGGUUCGCUUCCCGGACAGGAGGCAAGAGCAUUUUAUCAAGGGCCUGCCAGAAUACCACGUGGUGGGUCCAGUCCGAGUAGAUGCCAGUGGGCAUUUUUUGUCAUAUGGCUUGCACUAUCCCAUCACGAGCAGCAGGAGGAAGAGAGAUUUGGAUGGCUCAGAGGACUGGGUGUACUACAGAAUUUCUCACGAGGAGAAGGACCUGUUUUUUAACUUGACGGUCAAUCAAGGAUUUCUUUCCAAUAGCUACAUCAUGGAGAAGAGAUAUGGGAACCUCUCCCAUGUUAAGAUGAUGGCUUCCUCUGCCCCCCUCUGCCAUCUCAGUGGCACGGUUCUACAGCAGGGCACCAGAGUUGGGACGGCAGCCCUCAGUGCCUGCCAUGGACUGACUGGAUUUUUCCAACUACCACAUGGAGACUUUUUCAUUGAACCCGUGAAGAAGCAUCCACUGGUUGAGGGAGGGUACCACCCGCACAUCGUUUACAGGAGGCAGAAAGUUCCAGAAACCAAGGAGCCAACCUGUGGAUUAAAGGACAGUGUUAACAUCUCCCAGAAGCAAGAGCUAUGGCGGGAGAAGUGGGAGAGGCACAACUUGCCAAGCAGAAGCCUCUCUCGGCGUUCCAUCAGCAAGGAGAGAUGGGUGGAGACACUGGUGGUGGCCGACACAAAGAUGAUUGAAUACCAUGGGAGUGAGAAUGUGGAGUCCUACAUCCUCACCAUCAUGAACAUGGUCACUGGGUUGUUCCAUAACCCAAGCAUUGGCAAUGCAAUUCACAUUGUUGUGGUUCGGCUCAUUCUACUCGAAGAAGAAGAGCAAGGACUGAAAAUAGUUCACCAUGCAGAAAAGACACUGUCUAGCUUCUGCAAGUGGCAGAAGAGUAUCAAUCCCAAGAGUGACCUCAAUCCUGUUCAUCACGACGUGGCUGUCCUUCUCACCAGAAAGGACAUCUGUGCUGGUUUCAAUCGCCCCUGCGAGACCCUGGGCCUGUCUCACCUUUCAGGAAUGUGUCAGCCUCACCGCAGUUGUAACAUCAAUGAAGAUUCGGGACUCCCUCUGGCUUUCACAAUUGCCCAUGAGCUAGGACACAGCUUCGGCAUCCAGCAUGAUGGGAAAGAAAAUGACUGUGAGCCUGUGGGCAGACAUCCGUACAUCAUGUCCCGCCAGCUCCAGUACGAUCCCACUCCGCUGACAUGGUCCAAGUGCAGCGAGGAGUACAUCACCCGCUUCUUGGACCGAGGCUGGGGGUUCUGUCUUGAUGACAUACCUAAAAAGAAAGGCUUGAAGUCCAAGGUCAUUGCCCCCGGAGUGAUCUAUGAUGUUCACCACCAGUGCCAGCUACAAUAUGGACCCAAUGCUACCUUCUGCCAGGAAGUAGAAAACGUCUGCCAGACACUGUGGUGCUCCGUGAAGGGCUUUUGUCGCUCUAAGCUGGACGCUGCUGCAGAUGGAACUCAAUGUGGUGAGAAGAAGUGGUGUAUGGCAGGCAAGUGCAUCACAGUGGGGAAGAAACCAGAGAGCAUUCCUGGAGGCUGGGGCCGCUGGUCACCCUGGUCCCACUGUUCCAGGACCUGUGGGGCUGGAGUCCAGAGCGCAGAGAGGCUCUGCAACAACCCCGAGCCAAAGUUUGGAGGGAAAUAUUGCACUGGAGAAAGAAAACGCUAUCGCUUGUGCAACGUCCACCCCUGUCGCUCAGAGGCACCAACAUUUCGGCAGAUGCAGUGCAGUGAAUUUGACACUGUUCCCUACAAGAAUGAACUCUACCACUGGUUUCCCAUUUUUAACCCAGCACAUCCUUGUGAGCUCUACUGCCGACCCAUAGAUGGCCAGUUUUCUGAGAAAAUGCUGGAUGCUGUCAUUGAUGGUACCCCUUGCUUUGAAGGCGGCAACAGCAGAAAUGUCUGUAUUAAUGGCAUAUGUAAGAUGGUUGGCUGUGACUAUGAGAUCGAUUCCAAUGCCACCGAGGAUCGCUGCGGUGUGUGCCUGGGAGAUGGCUCUUCCUGCCAGACUGUGAGAAAGAUGUUUAAGCAGAAGGAAGGAUCUGGUUAUGUUGACAUUGGGCUCAUUCCAAAAGGAGCAAGGGACAUAAGAGUGAUGGAAAUUGAGGGAGCUGGAAACUUCCUGGCCAUCAGGAGUGAAGAUCCUGAAAAAUAUUACCUGAAUGGAGGGUUUAUUAUCCAGUGGAACGGGAACUAUAAGCUGGCAGGGACUGUCUUUCAGUAUGACAGGAAAGGAGACCUGGAAAAGCUGAUGGCCACAGGUCCCACCAAUGAGUCUGUGUGGAUCCAGCUUCUAUUCCAGGUGACUAACCCUGGCAUCAAGUAUGAGUACACAAUCCAGAAAGAUGGCCUUGACAAUGAUGUUGAGCAGCAGAUGUACUUCUGGCAGUACGGCCACUGGACAGAGUGCAGUGUGACCUGCGGGACAGGUAUCCGCCGCCAAACUGCCCAUUGCAUAAAGAAGGGCCGCGGGAUGGUGAAAGCUACAUUCUGUGACCCAGAAACACAGCCCAAUGGGAGACAGAAGAAGUGCCAUGAAAAGGCUUGUCCACCCAGGUGGUGGGCAGGGGAGUGGGAAGCAUGCUCGGCGACAUGCGGGCCCCACGGGGAGAAGAAGCGAACCGUGCUGUGCAUCCAGACCAUGGUCUCUGACGAGCAGGCUCUCCCGCCCACAGACUGCCAGCACCUGCUGAAGCCCAAGACCCUCCUUUCCUGCAACAGAGACAUCCUGUGCCCCUCGGACUGGACAGUGGGCAACUGGAGUGAGCUUCACUGGUUGGGUCCAAACACAGUUCGACACUCCUUCAGCUGUACAUUCUCCUGUGCUCACAGCAUCUGCUUUUCAAAAGAGCUGAUUUCACAGAGCUGUUUUACAUCAUGUUCUGUUUCCUGUGGUGGUGGAGUGCGGAUUCGCAGUGUCACAUGUGCCAAGAACCAUGAUGAACCUUGCGAUGUGACAAGGAAACCCAACAGCCGAGCUCUGUGUGGCCUCCAGCAAUGCCCUUCUAGCCGGAGAGUUCUGAAACCAAACAAAGGCACUAUUUCCAAUGGAAAAAACCCACCAACACUAAAGCCCGUCCCUCCACCUACAUCCAGGCCCAGAAUGCUGACCACACCCACAGGGCCUGAGUCUAUGAGCACAAGCACUCCAGCAAUCAGCAGCCCUAGUCCUACCACAGCCUCCAAAGAAGGAGACCUGGGUGGGAAACAGUGGCAAGAUAGCUCAACCCAACCUGAGCUGAGCUCUCGCUAUCUCAUUUCCACUGGAAGCACUUCCCAGCCCAUCCUCACUUCCCAAUCCUUGAGCAUUCAGCCAAGUGAGGAAAAUGUUUCCAGUUCAGAUACUGGUCCUACCUCGGAGGGAGGCCUUGUAGCUACAACAACAAGUGGUUCUGGCUUGUCAUCUUCCCGCAACCCUAUCACUUGGCCUGUGACUCCAUUUUACAAUACCUUGACCAAAGGUCCAGAAAUGGAGAUUCACAGUGGCUCAGGGGAAGAAAGAGAACAGCCUGAGGACAAAGAUGAAAGCAAUCCUGUAAUAUGGACCAAGAUCAGAGUACCUGGAAAUGACGCUCCAGUGGAAAGUACAGAAAUGCCACUUGCACCUCCACUAACACCAGAUCUCAGCAGGGAGUCCUGGUGGCCACCCUUCAGCACAGUAAUGGAAGGACUGCUCCCCAGCCAAAGGCCCACUACUUCCGAAACUGGGACACCCAGAGUUGAGGGGAUGGUUACUGAAAAGCCAGCCAACACUCUGCUCCCUCUGGGAGGAGACCACCAGCCAGAACCCUCAGGAAAGACGGCAAACCGUAACCACCUGAAACUUCCAAACAACAUGAACCAAACAAAAAGUUCUGAACCAGUCCUGACUGAGGAGGAUGCAACAAGUCUGAUUACUGAGGGCUUUUUGCUAAAUGCCUCCAAUUACAAGCAGCUCACAAACGGCCACGGCUCUGCACACUGGAUCGUCGGAAACUGGAGCGAGUGCUCCACCACAUGUGGCCUGGGGGCCUACUGGAGAAGGGUGGAGUGCAGCACCCAGAUGGAUUCUGACUGUGCGGCCAUCCAGAGACCUGACCCUGCAAAAAGAUGCCACCUCCGUCCCUGUGCUGGCUGGAAAGUGGGAAACUGGAGCAAGUGCUCCAGAAACUGCAGUGGGGGCUUCAAGAUACGCGAGAUUCAGUGCGUGGACAGCCGGGACCACCGGAACCUGAGGCCAUUUCACUGCCAGUUCCUGGCCGGCAUUCCUCCCCCAUUGAGCAUGAGCUGUAACCCGGAGCCCUGUGAGGCGUGGCAGGUGGAGCCUUGGAGCCAGUGCUCCAGGUCCUGUGGAGGUGGAGUUCAGGAGAGAGGAGUGUUCUGUCCAGGAGGCCUCUGUGAUUGGACAAAAAGACCCACAUCCACCAUGUCUUGCAAUGAGCACCUGUGCUGUCACUGGGCCACUGGGAACUGGGACCUGUGUUCCACUUCCUGUGGAGGUGGCUUUCAGAAGAGGACUGUCCAAUGUGUGCCCUCAGAGGGCAAUAAAACUGAAGACCAAGACCAAUGUCUAUGUGAUCACAAACCCAGACCUCCAGAAUUCAAAAAAUGCAACCAGCAGGCCUGCAAGAAAAGUGCCGAUUUACUUUGCACUAAGGACAAACUGUCAGCCAGUUUCUGCCAGACACUGAAAGCCAUGAAGAAAUGUUCUGUGCCCACCGUGAGGGCUGAGUGCUGCUUCUCGUGUCCCCAGACACACAUCACACACACCCAAAGGCAAAGAAGGCAACGGUUGCUCCAAAAGUCAAAAGAACUCUAAGCCCAAAAGGAAGCCAGCUUCCACCAGACUGCAGCAGCCUGCUGACCAUGACAUGCUUUAGCCCUGGGAGCUGCUUCGUUGAGGUUUUGCUUCAUAUAUUUCAGAUUCAGCUUUGGGUCAUGAUGAAACAAAAUCCAUUGUGUUCCUCUAGCCACCGAAUGUCCCUCACAGGAGGCCUAGGCUGCCGUACUUGCUGCUCCCUGAUAGGAAGGUGAAAUAGCUAGGAGAAUCAGGCAGCACCUGGUAUCGGCUCCUGGGAAAGGUGCCAGGUUAGACAGAUUUGUGAAAUACUGUAUUUUUGUUCUCCCUUAAAGAUAAAAACAAAGAGACCAGCUAUUUCCCUGACUACCUCAAGAGUAUCAGGCAACACUUACCCAGGGGACAAAUAAUCUUCUUAAUUUAUCUUGAUGAAUACCUUUCUUUUUUUUUUCUUGCCUCCCUGCCUGGGGCAGCUGCUAUUUAAAAUGUCACAGCGGAGCUUUAGGAACAUUCCUUUAAUUCAUCCAGGCAGAGGACUGCUUUCUUCACCCCAUGUUCAACUAGGGCAGGAAGUGCUGGUUACAUCCCUCAGUCUCUUCCUCCAUCCCUGUAGGGCUCCAUAUCUGGGCUGCUUAGAGUCUCCUGCCAACCUUGGGACACUAGACUAAGAGGAAACAGGCAUAAGAAACACAGCCUAAGGGGUUUAGGUCACUUACACAGAAAACACUUCUGGUUUGAAGAGCAUUUCUAUGAAAACUCGUAAAAUGCAAAUGAGCAGAAAUCAAUUUCUUAAUAUUACAGAAAAGGAACUGUGGGCCUUUAUUCUUCCCACUUUCCUGGCAAAUACACACUCCUUUGCAGAAGGGAAAAUGUGUCUUCCUGGCUGACUUCCUCCCAUCCUCCAGUCCCCACAGGAGGCCUGAGCUCAGGUCCCACCAUCGUCUUGCUGCAGGGGCUGUAUAUGCAAAGACCACUAUGACCAGCUCUAGGGCUGCCACCUGUCCUCACCUCUUCUCAGGUUGGAAAAUGGAGGUUCCAUAUUAAAAUAUUUCAAAGAACCAGGUAAAUUGUACUAAGUACAAGAACAUAGUGCAAACUUCUAAUCUAGAGAAAAAACAUUUCUAAAAAGUAAGGUAAAGGGGAUCUACUCCUCAGUGUACCCAAUAUGUAGUUAGUCUUAAAGAUCUUUUACUUUGGGGAGAACAGGUGAAUCAGGGAGUCCAAAGAAACUGAAAUGAAAGUUAGAAUGCUUGUUCUGGAUGUUCCUACCUCCCACCAGAAGUCAAAGUAGGCUUGGUCUCAAAUUCAGAGCAAAUUUCUAGACAAAGUGAUUUCUAAGGGAAGGUACUUACAUGAACUGAACCCAGAGAAAGAGGGUAAGUGGGUGGGUGGAGGGGCAUAAGCUUCAAAUGAAAGAAGAUAUCAGAACCAAUUCUUGACAGGGAGAAAGGCAAGGAUGUGGCCUUCAUGUGAUGGGCAGCAUAUUUUCUGACUCAUGCACAGAUACACUUAAUACUCCUCAUGGAACACAAUAUCCCACGUCUCCCUUUACCUAUCCGUUCAGCAGAAUGGUGCUAUUAAAAAAAUGGUGCUAAUAUCUAGAUGGUGGCAGAAUUAAUGUAAACAUAGAUAGGCAUACAAAUGGGUAAGUGUAUGUGAAACUCUCCAUAUACAUCUUCUGUUAAACAUGUAACGGUGUUGCUGACCAAUGCCAGUUUUAUUGCUUGGGUACCUUGAAUUUAAGAUUUAAUAUUAUGUGCUUUUUAUUUUUUUCCAAGCCAUUAACGUGUAUUACUCUCAUGAAUUCCUGUGAAAAAUAAAACAGUGGGAUUGGGAUGAAAUUCAAGAUAGACCAGAAACAGGAGGAAAGUACAAAUGUUUACCUAAAGCCAGAGAAUUUAUUUCUAGAUGAUAAUUACAUUAUUGUAUUCUCUGCCUUUAAACAUAAACAUUGCUGGCCGAUAGCAAUCUCUGGUGAAUAAUGGUUUUCGAGGAGAGGAGACACUUAAAUUGUUAGUGACAUGAGUGGAGGAGAAUCUGAUAUUUACUAAUGAGGCAGUUUGCAAAGACUGUCCCUGAAGUGUAGUGUAGUCUUUCAGGGGGAUUCAUUUAGUAAGCUAGAUUGAUUUAACCUGGUACUGUACUAGCAUAGGGUCAAAUACGUGUCAUCAGAGACCUGGGUAUGACCAGGCUUACAAAACUCAGGAACAAACUCAGAUUCCUACUGACCUCAACCAACUAAACUAGGCCAAAUUUCUCCGUGUACAAAAUGGACCACGUUAUUUACAAUCCACGUGGUGGAGAAGAUGGUAGACAUGUGGAGAGAGUUUGGCCAGGUGCUCCAUUCUAGGUCUUUUUCCAGUUUCUCAAAGGCAGAACAUUGGCUCCUAAUUAUUUGCCAUGGAUAUUUGCUUCCUGUUCUGGAGCUAUGUUGUAAGACAGCUGUGUGAUGUCCAUCAUUCUUGACUCCAGAAUGAAGACAGGGCUUGCUGUUUUCUGUCCUGUUGGUAUCAUCUGUUGCCUUGGCGAUCACUCAGUGAUGAGUCGUCAGUAUUUUGACAUGUCCCAGUGCUUGCUGUACAAGAGGGGACUCAGAUCAACAGGAAGACUCUGAAGACAGGAACCUGCAUGGUAUCUUACAUCUUUGAUACUUGGGUGCUGAUAUGAAGCAGAGUUGUUGAUUUACUUUAUCUAGGCCCUUCUUUCUUCUCACCUGGAUCAAGCAACUGAGAAGUGUAUCAGGAGACACUGGAUACAUAUCUCUAUGAAAUAGAGAGGGCCAUCGCAGGGCCUGGUACUUAACUACAUUAACGUUCUAAAACCCAGUUUGGUUUACGUUGUCUUUCACAGUAGUAUAUUUAGCUCUUCUCUGGAAAGUUGUGGGUUAAUAUAAUUCUUAAACAUGAAAAUGUAAUUAAACACACCACGAGAGAACAAUAUUCCAGGAGACUUAAUAGUGAUUACUUUCUUCAAUCAGGAAAUCGUUUCAGUGCCUCCUUUGUAGGAAUGCUUUGUUUUGUGAUGGGUUUUCUUAAAGAAGAGCACACCUCCGUCCAAUCUCCUGAGACAGCCACGUCUCCGCUGACAUCCCACUGUGAUGCUUUCAGAUAGUCAGUGAAUGUUUCUGAUAACCUUCAUCCAGUAUCUGAAACACAAUGUGAGAGAUUAUAUUGUUUUAGAUAAUAACAUCCCAUUUAGUUGACUAAAAUCUUCCAAACUCUGAAAGCUGCACACUGCUACUCCAGAGAGUGCAGGUCUUAGCUCUUCUCCUUUCUGACUUCAAGAUGAAUCUUUGGGACGAUGUUUCUGGUGCUUGGUCCACAGUGAUUCACUUUUGAAGGAGAGGCCACAUGACAUGAACUGCCUGGUGUUACAACCUAGCUAACAUAUUUGAUGCUACUCCUGUUGUCUGUACUGCUUAUUCAAGUAGUAUUCUAAGUUAUGUUACUAAAAAACAUGGUGGGUAAAGCACAAUCCUACCCAUCAUUGUCCUCCAAAAUAAUUGUAUGACAUACACGGCCCAGCCCAUUGCCCUCCCUGCAUCUCUGUGCUGCUUUGCCAUUUCCCCUUCUACCCAGCCUCCUCAAGGGGUACCUUGGUGGAUAUUUCAGUACUUAAAACCAGACUGUAAUCAUAACCUCCCUCUGUGUGGCAUCAAUAAAUAGCCAAACUCA